AAACCACGUGGACGCGUCUGGGCUGCUGGAGGCAGCCCGAGCCGCCGCCGUCGGUGUCGCCGCCACCACCACCAUCGGAGUCACGAGUCCCGCGUCUGUCCGAAGUCGCCGCUCUCGGGCUGCUCACGUCUCUUCGGAGAGCGCGCACAUGGCGACUCAGGCGCACUCCCUCAGCUACGCAGGGUGCAACUUCUUGCGCCAACGUCUGGUCCUGUCUACCCUGAGCGGGCGCCCCGUCAAAAUCCGAAAGAUUCGGGCCAGAGACGACAACCCGGGCCUCCGAGAUUUUGAAGCCAGCUUCAUAAGGCUAUUGGACAAAAUAACGAAUGGUUCUCGAAUUGAAAUAAACCAAACAGGAACAACCUUAUAUUAUCAGCCUGGCCUCCUGUAUGGUGGAUCUGUGGAACAUGACUGUAGCGUCCUUCGUGGCAUUGGGUAUUACCUGGAGAGUCUUCUUUGCUUGGCUCCAUUUAUGAAGCACCCGUUAAAAAUAGUUCUACGAGGAGUGACCAAUGAUCAGGUUGACCCUUCAGUUGAUGUUCUUAAGGCAACAGCACUCCCUUUGUUGAAACAAUUUGGGAUUGAUGGUGAAUCAUUUGAACUGAAGAUUGUGCGACGGGGAAUGCCUCCCGGAGGAGGAGGCGAAGUGGUUUUCUCAUGUCCUGUGAGGAAGGUCUUGAAGCCCAUUCAACUCACAGAUCCAGGAAAAAUCAAACGUAUUAGAGGAAUGGCGUACUCUGUACGUGUGUCACCUCAGAUGGCGAACCGGAUUGUGGAUUCUGCAAGGAGCAUCCUCAACAAGUUCAUACCUGAUAUCUAUAUUUACACAGAUCACAUGAAAGGAGUCAACUCUGGGAAGUCUCCGGGCUUUGGGUUGUCACUGGUUGCUGAGACCACCAGUGGCACCUUCCUCAGUGCUGAACUGGCCUCCAACCCCCAGGGCCAGGGAGCAGCAGUACUUCCAGAGGACCUUGGCAGGAACUGUGCCCGGCUGCUGCUGGAGGAAAUCUACAGGGGUGGAUGCGUAGACUCGACCAACCAAAGCCUGGCGCUACUACUCAUGACCCUUGGACAGCAGGAUGUUUCCAAAGUCCUGCUAGGCCCUCUCUCUCCCUACACGAUAGAAUUUUUGCGGCAUUUGAAGAGCUUUUUCCAGAUUAUGUUUAAAAUUGAAACCAAGCCAUGUGGUGAAGAACUCAAGGGUGGGGAUAAAGUGCUGAUGACCUGUGUUGGCAUUGGUUUCUCCAACCUUAGCAAGACCCUCAAGUGAUAACCAUCACAAGAUAAGGCCCCAAUGCCUACAGACAAAGCAGAAGCUGCCACGGACACCAAUGGGACCAAGUCCAAAUGGAUUAAUCCAGGACAGAAUAGCCACUUGCUUAAUUUUCUGUGAAGAAAUAUCAAUAUACAAAUAAAAGACAUCCCUGUAGCAUAUGGUUUCCAGCUGUUUCUCCAGUGGCAUUGCCAUUGCCCAGGAGGGGCCCAGUCACCAUGAGAGCUCCCUUGCCUUACCUGGAGGAAGAAUGUGCCUUCAGGCCACAGUCGUGCUGCUAGAACAGUCUCGUAGCUGCAGUUCAGCUGUGCUUCCUCAGCCUACUAUCAUAGGCUUCCUCAGCCCUCUGUCAUAUGGCUGUUUUGCAAACCUGUGGAGUCUGUUACUGUUCUUUCUGCAAGGACUCACCUCCUUGAGCCUUGGUUUUUGUUGUAGGGAUUAAAUGAGAUAAUAUGAGUGGCAGCUCUUCAUGAGUCCUGCAGUGCUAAGCAAAUGUCAGAAAUUGGUGUAUUAGACUAUUUAUCUUUGAUCUUCUGAAUGGAUUGCUGUCAUGGACACGGACACGGAUCUUCAUCUGGUUCAUUGUAUUUAUAUGUGAGGGAUGGAUGGCUGCGGGGCUCCAAGUAAGUUAUUGGGAUGUUUUUAUAUUCCAGGUGUGCUGUACAUUCUUAUUUUAUUUUCACAAUAGCUCUGUGAUGUAAGUGCUAUCUCCAUGAGAAAAUUCAUAAAGGGUGUUUUGUUCCUUUGAAAUGUAUAAUGUAAAGACAUUAAAUCUCCUCAUUUAAGGA